CUCUUCCGAGCGGGGUCACGGCCCGGCCGUCGGUAACCUGGUUUCCGAGAGUGCCGGGCGGUCGGCGGGUCAGGGCAGCCCGGGGCCUGACGCCAUGUCCCGGAACCUGCGCACCGCGCUCAUUUUCGGCGGCUUCAUCUCCCUGAUCGGCGCCGCCUUCUAUCCCAUCUACUUCCGGCCCCUAAUGAGAUUGGAGGAGUACAAGAAGGAACAAGCUAUAAAUCGGGCUGGAAUUGUUCAAGAGGAUGUGCAGCCACCAGGGUUAAAAGUGUGGUCUGAUCCAUUUGGCAGGAAAUGAGAGGGCUGUCAUCAGCUCUGAUUAAGAAAGGAGAUUUCUUCAUGCUUUCGAUUCUGCAUGGGGUACAGCCAGUCACCUCACCAGAGAAUGACGGCUGGAGAAGAAAACUCUGUAAUACCAUAAAUAAGAGUGCUUGUAAUAAAAGACUGUGCACAAGGAUUAAUAUUUCCCUUCUUAAGUAUCAAAAGAACUCUGGAACAAAUUAUACCAUUAGGAAGGUUUUCAUGAUUCAGUUGAUUUUCCAAAAAUGAAGCUAUCUCACCCAGCUGGGUUUGGAGGAGCAAUCUGCUUAUUAUUCUGUCGUUACCACUUACUCAAGCGAGCUGUGAUAUGAAUACAAGCAACCAGUGGGCUCGGGAAGGUCCGGGUCUCUUCUGCCAUCUUCCAGAUAAGAGAUUUCAGUAAAAAACUGCCAUGCUGAGCUGCCUUAUAGAGCUCUUCGAAAAUGUUCGAGUUGAUAAAGCUCUUUGAGGACAAGGUACUUCGUGCACCUCAUGCUGAAGAUUGCACCGUGUUGGAAAAUAAAUAUGAAGCAAGUCAAACUAGAUGCAUACACUUGUGUAGAAAUCAAUAAUCAAUUAAUAGAAGUGAAAAAAUAGACAUUAAAAUGAUUUAUUUCUA